ACUGGCAACCCAGGGAAGCUCCAGGCUUGGGGGCCGGAUGUGACGUCACUGACGUGCGCACUGGGGGUCAGAGAGAAGGGAGAGGCCUCCUUCUGAGGGGCGGCUUGAUACCGGUGGAGGUAAGCUGGCCGAGGCUCUGUGAGGAGUCAAGGAGCUCCAGGAAGCAGGCAGGCCUUGGUCUGAGACAGUGUCCUCAGGUCGCAGAGCAGAGGAGACCCAGGCAGUGUCAGCAGUGAAGGUUCUCGGGACAGGCUAACCAGGAGGACAGGAGCCCCAAGAGGCCCCAGAGCAGCACUGACGAAGACCUGCCUGUGGGUCUCCAUCGCCCAGCUCCUGCCCACGCUCCUGACUGCUGCCCUGACCAGAGUCAUCAUGUCUCUCGAGCAGAGGAGUCCGCACUGCAAGCCUGAUGAAGACCUUGAAGCCCAAGGAGAGGACUUGGGCCUGAUGGGUGCACAGGAACCCACAGGCGAGGAGGAGGAGACUACCUCCUCCUCUGACAGCAAGGAGGAGGAGGUGUCUGCUGCUGGGUCAUCAAGUCCUCCCCAGAGUCCUCAGGGAGGCGCUUCCUCCUCCAUUUCCGUCUACUACACUUUAUGGAGCCAAUUCGAUGAGGGCUCCAGCAGUCAAGAAGAGGAAGAGCCAAGCUCCUCGGUCGACCCAGCUCAGCUGGAGUUCAUGUUCCAAGAAGCACUGAAAUUGAAGGUGGCUGAGUUGGUUCAUUUCCUGCUCCACAAAUAUCGAGUCAAGGAGCCGGUCACAAAGGCAGAAAUGCUGGAGAGCGUCAUCAAAAAUUACAAGCGCUACUUUCCUGUGAUCUUCGGCAAAGCCUCCGAGUUCAUGCAGGUGAUCUUUGGCACUGAUGUGAAGGAGGUGGACCCCGCCGGCCACUCCUACAUCCUUGUCACUGCUCUUGGCCUCUCGUGCGAUAGCAUGCUGGGUGAUGGUCAUAGCAUGCCCAAGGCCGCCCUCCUGAUCAUUGUCCUGGGUGUGAUCCUAACCAAAGACAACUGCGCCCCUGAAGAGGUUAUCUGGGAAGCGUUGAGUGUGAUGGGGGUGUAUGUUGGGAAGGAGCACAUGUUCUACGGGGAGCCCAGGAAGCUGCUCACCCAAGAUUGGGUGCAGGAAAACUACCUGGAGUACCGGCAGGUGCCCGGCAGUGAUCCUGCGCACUACGAGUUCCUGUGGGGUUCCAAGGCCCACGCUGAAACCAGCUAUGAGAAGGUCAUAAAUUAUUUGGUCAUGCUCAAUGCAAGAGAGCCCAUCUGCUACCCAUCCCUUUAUGAAGAGGUUUUGGGAGAGGAGCAAGAGGGAGUCUGAGCACCAGCCGCAGCCGGGGCCAAAGUUUGUGGGGUCAGGGCCCCAUCCAGCAGCUGCCCUGCCCCAUGUGACAUGAGGCCCAUUCUUCGCUCUGUGUUUGAAGAGAGCAAUCAGUGUUCUCAGUGGCAGUGGGUGGAAGUGAGCACACUGUAUGUCAUCUCUGGGUUCCUUGUCUAUUGGGUGAUUUGGAGAUUUAUCCUUGCUCCCUUUUGGAAUUGUUCAAAUGUUCUUUUAAUGGUCAGUUUAAUGAACUUCACCAUCGAAGUUAAUGAAUGACAGUAGUCACACAUAUUGCUGUUUAUGUUAUUUAGGAGUAAGAUUCUUGCUUUUGAGUCACAUGGGGAAAUCCCUGUUAUUUUGUGAAUUGGGACAAGAUAACAUAGCAGAGGAAUUAAUAAUUUUUUUGAAACUUGAACUUAGCAGCAAAAUAGAGCUCAUAAAGAAAUAGUGAAAUGAAAAUGUAGUUAAUUCUUGCCUUAUACCUCUUUCUCUCUCCUGUAAAAUUAAAACAUAUACAUGUAUACCUGGAUUUGCUUGGCUUCUUUGAGCAUGUAAGAGAAAUAAAAAUUGAAAGAAUAA